GAGACGCGACCAGGACGCGGGGAGGACGGACCAGCAGGACAGACCGACCGGGGGCCCGGCGGGCGGAGGGCAGCGCAGCCACGUCCCCCCUGGAUCCGCCGUCAGCCGGGCCCGGGGCUUUCGACAUGCCCCCCAGGAGAGUGUGCUGGGCAGACGAUGCUGGACACGAUGGAGGCGCCCGGCCACUCCAGGCAGCUGCUGCUGCAGCUCAACAACCAGCGCACCAAGGGCUUCUUGUGCGACGUGAUCAUCGUGGUGCAGAACGCCCUCUUCCGCGCGCACAAGAACGUGCUGGCGGCCAGCAGCGCCUACCUCAAGUCCCUGGUGGUGCAUGACAACCUGCUCAACCUGGACCAUGACAUGGUGAGCCCGGCCGUGUUCCGCCUGGUGCUGGACUUCAUCUACACCGGCCGCCUGGCUGACGGCGCAGAGGCGGCUGCGGCCGCGGCCGUGGCCCCGGGGGCUGAGCCGAGCCUGGGCGCCGUGCUGGCCGCCGCCAGCUACCUGCAGAUCCCCGACCUCGUGGCGCUGUGCAAGAAACGCCUCAAGCGCCACGGCAAGUACUGCCACCUGCGGGGCGGCGGCGGCGGCGGCGGCGGCUACGCGCCCUAUGGUCGGCCGGGCCGGGGCCUGCGGGCCGCCACGCCGGUCAUCCAGGCCUGCUACCCGUCCCCAGUCGGGCCUCCGCCGCCGCCUGCCGCGGAGCCGCCCUCGGGCCCAGAGGCCGCGGUCAACACGCACUGCGCCGAGCUGUACGCGUCGGGACCCGGCCCGGCCGCCGCACUCUGUGCCUCGGAGCGCCGCUGCUCCCCUCUUUGUGGCCUGGACCUGUCCAAGAAGAGCCCGCCGGGCUCCGCGGCGCCAGAGCGGCCGCUGGCUGAGCGCGAGCUGCCCCCGCGCCCGGACAGCCCUCCCAGCGCCGGCCCCGCCGCCUACAAGGAGCCGCCUCUCGCCCUGCCGUCGCUGCCGCCGCUGCCCUUCCAGAAGCUGGAGGAGGCCGCACCGCCUUCCGACCCAUUUCGCGGCGGCAGCGGCAGCCCGGGACCCGAGCCCCCCGGCCGCCCCGACGGGCCUAGUCUCCUCUAUCGCUGGAUGAAGCACGAGCCGGGCCUGGGUAGCUAUGGCGACGAGCUGGGCCGGGAGCGCGGCUCCCCCAGCGAGCGCUGCGAAGAGCGUGGUGGGGACGCGGCCGUCUCGCCCGGGGGGCCCCCGCUCGGCCUGGCGCCGCCGCCGCGCUACCCUGGCAGCCUGGACGGGCCCGGCGCGGGCGGCGACGGCGACGACUACAAGAGCAGCAGCGAGGAGACCGGUAGCAGCGAGGACCCCAGCCCGCCUGGCGGCCACCUCGAGGGCUACCCAUGCCCGCACCUGGCCUAUGGCGAGCCCGAGAGCUUCGGUGACAACCUGUACGUGUGCAUUCCGUGCGGCAAGGGCUUCCCCAGCUCUGAGCAGCUGAACGCGCACGUGGAGGCUCACGUGGAGGAGGAGGAAGCGCUGUACGGCAGGGCCGAGGCGGCCGAAGUGGCCGCUGGGGCCGCCGGCCUAGGGCCCCCUUUUGGAGGCGGCGGGGACAAGGUCGCCGGGGCUCCGGGUGGCCUGGGAGAGCUGCUGCGGCCCUACCGCUGCGCGUCGUGCGACAAGAGCUACAAGGACCCGGCCACGCUGCGGCAGCACGAGAAGACGCACUGGCUGACCCGGCCCUACCCAUGCACCAUCUGCGGGAAGAAGUUCACGCAGCGUGGGACCAUGACGCGCCACAUGCGCAGCCACCUGGGCCUCAAGCCCUUCGCGUGCGACGCGUGCGGCAUGCGGUUCACGCGCCAGUACCGCCUCACGGAGCACAUGCGCAUCCACUCGGGCGAGAAGCCCUACGAGUGCCAGGUGUGCGGCGGCAAGUUCGCACAGCAACGCAACCUCAUCAGCCACAUGAAGAUGCACGCCGUGGGGGGCGCGGCCGGCGCGGCCGGGGCGCUGGCGGGCUUGGGGGGGCUCCCCGGCGUCCCCGGCCCCGACGGCAAGGGCAAGCUCGACUUCCCCGAGGGCGUCUUUGCUGUGGCUCGCCUCACGGCCGAGCAGCUGAGCCUGAAGCAGCAGGACAAGGCGGCCGCGGCCGAGCUGCUGGCGCAGACCACGCACUUCCUGCACGACCCCAAGGUGGCGCUGGAGAGCCUCUACCCGCUGGCCAAGUUCACGGCCGAGCUGGGCCUCAGCCCCGACAAGGCGGCCGAGGUGCUGAGCCAGGGCGCUCACCUGGCGGCCGGGCCCGACGGCCGGACCAUCGACCGUUUCUCUCCCACCUAGAGCGCCCCUCGCCAGCCCGCUCUGUCGCUGCUGCGCGGCCCUGGCCCGCACCCCAGGGAGCGGCGGGGGCGGCGCGCAGGGCCCACUGUGCCCGGGACAACCGCAGCGUCGCCACAGUGGCGGCUCCACCUCUCGGCGGCCUCACCUGGCCUCACUGCUUCGUGCCUUAGCUCGGGGGUCGGGGGAGAACCCCGGGACGGGGGUGGGAUGGGGUAAGGGAAAUUUAUAUUUUUGAUAUCAGCUUUGACCAAAGGAGACCCCAGGCCCCUCCCGCCUCUUCCUGUGGUUCGUCGGCCCCCUCCCCCGGCUCCGCGCUGCUCUUAGAGGGGGAGGGGUGUCACUGUCGGGGCACUCCUAGCCCUACCUCCGGCCCUUGCGACCACACCCAUUCUCACUGUGAAUCUCCCCGCUGGGGUCGGAGCGUCGGGCAGAGUUGGGGAGUGGGGAGGGGACUGAGCCGGCCGGAGGGCCCCCCGCACCCCCGCUCCCACCCACCCCGGGACUGAUAAUGUGAAGUUCCUCAUUUUGCACAAGUGGCACUAGCCCCAGGGCCAACCCUUCCUUCCUCAGUCACCAAGGGCGGGGAGUUCUGGAGUCGGAAGGCGAAGAGCCUACCACCAGGUCUCCCACUCCCGCGGUGCCCUCCCUUCCCUUCCCUGCGGCCCCGGACCAUAUUUAUUGCAUGCGCCCCGGCGGCCCCCCAUCCCGAGCCCAGGCUGGGCUGGGCUGGAACGCGGUCUCUUUAGCUCCCUCCUCUUCGUUUGUAUAUUUCCUACCUUGUACACAGGCUCUUCCAGAGCCGCUUCCAUUUUCUAUACUCGAACCAAACAGCAAUAAAGCAGUAACCAAGGACCCCGACCCCGCUGCUCUCUUCUGCCCCUGCACAAGGACCUGGAUGGGCUGCGCCCGCUGGGUGGAGGAGCCAGAAAGGGCCACCCUCACACAGGUGCAGAGGCUUGGACCUGCCUCCCUCCCCAGUCCCAGAAACAGAUCAGCAAGAGGUCAGGUAUGUUUCAUAACUAAAAAUUUAUUAAGGAAACAAAACCAGUGCUGCAAACGGGACAGAAAGGAGAGCUGGGUCUCCCUCCCGACCACCCAGUCAUCGGCCUUCCAGCUGGGGAGAGAAUCUUAAAGGAGAGGCCGGGGACCCUGUACUCCAAAGAGCCCAGUCUUCUGAGACUCUAGGGGACUCCUACCCCCAAACUACUGGCCUUGGCUCCCCUACACGGUACCCCAUCGCUUCUGGCAUAGUCCUGGGCCUCAGGGAGGGCAGAGCUGCGCACCCAUCCUCCAGGCAGGCUGUGCAGUCAGGCCAUGGGCUCUGGGGUAUCCCCCACUGGUCCCAUUAAGAUUUGCCCCUGGCUCCACCGAAAACCCCGUCUUCCCCUAAGUUGUCCUUGUCUCUGGCCCUGGGUUUCAGGAACUCAUUCUUGGUAAGGAAGCCUCCCCACUGAGGUACCAGCUAAAGGGGCAAGGAAAGGGCCCCUGUGUCAGUGUCAGUUUUUCCGGGGAGUGAGGGCAAAGCUAGAAACCAGGUUAGGCGACGGUGCCCCAGCACUGGAAUGCCUCAGGCUGGGCUGUCCACGCCUGGAAGUUUCUCCCAGCACAGGAGCCGAGGGUGGAAGGCCCUGGGUGGGAGACCUGUACUAGGUUCCUGCCAUGGGUAGUAGAGAGGGAAAGUUCAGAGUGAGAACCCCUAUGACGAGGAACCGCGGUGAAGAAAUGAAGGGGAUCAGGGAGGUGAAAAGGAUCAACUAGAAGGGGAAGAAGGGUGAGGGGCUAUUCUGGAGGGAGGGUAGGCGGGCAAGGAGGGGUGAAGGGGGAGCUGAGGGGAGUCAGGACAUUUCCUGAAGAGGAAGCUAGACGGAAAGAAAGGCCAGUGAGGAGAGAGGGAGCAGGUGGAGGCCACCCGAGAGCACGGGCCUGAGACCAGAUGCCCCUUUCCUCUAGACUCAUGACUGUCCACGGGGACGCAACUGGCGAAGUGUGAGGGACCCAGGUUGAUAAGGGCAGGAAGAGGAGCAGCAGGAAGGGUGUGUGGUAAGUCUGGGGUGGAUGGUAGAAGAGGUGGGGGCCCAGGGCUGCUGUUAGGGACAUGCUGUCUAGAAGCCGACUUGGGUUCAUGGGCGAGUCCAGGCCUCAGGGAGACUGGGGACACACACCCUGGGCACUUCUUCCUGACUUAACCAAAGCCUCUUGAACACAUUCACGACAGAGGUUCUGAAGAUGAAAGGGAACUGUGAUUUCACUGCAUCUGACGGAAACUCAGAACCCCUGCCCUGUCUCCACUGGAGAAAGUGGCUGCGUCCCCAGGCGAGAAGGCCCUCCCUCAGCCUUGGAAUGAGACGGGGGAGGGAGAAAGGCUGAGAGCAUGGGCGGCCUAUCUGGCUUGCCCAGCUGCUGUUGCUGUAGCCAGCCACCUCCCUGCUAAAUCCUGGCAGCCCAGGAGGGUCCCAGCAGCUUCCGCCCGAUCCUUGGGAGGGGCUCUGUGAGGAGCAGGUCCCCCACAGCAUGGCCGUGGCGUGGGUUGGAAGAGGAUGGUUUAUUGUCUGGGUGGAUUGGUGGCUCAGGCACGUGGGCAUCUUCCGUGCUACACUGGGCGCCUGGUGGCCUUUCAGGAACGGUUCCACGGGGGGGGGGCCCCAGUGUGGCUCCCUCAGCCCACCUGGGCCCACGUGAGGAAGGCUGGGAUGUCCCGUACAGGAACAUUCCUUGUGAGCGCCUUCACACGCAGGUUCCGGUCAUCCGUCAACAGCACCACCUCCCGCAGUAGCCGGAUUGGCUCCUCUGUGGGCAUGAGAGAGCAGAAGGCUGUCACUGAGGACAGGAGGCAGAGGGCUGGCUGCUCUUCUCACCCUGGAGAAUGUGGUCCUGGGGAGGGGGUGCCACGCUAGCCGUGUCUUGGCUCUUCUACCAGUCCUUUCCUCCGUCCGGGCUCUCAGCCCCGGGGACCCUCCCCUGCUGGCCUAGAGAGGGCUGCACUGGGCUUCUGCCUUGACUCCGGCCUCCCAUACAGGACUCUCUUCUGCCUAGUUCCCAAAAGCUGCCCAAACCCGUCAGCCUCCCAGGACCCUAAACUGAGGGAAUAGAAGCAGCCCCUUGACCUCUACUCCUUUUUACCACAUGGCUGGCCCCCAGAUCACAACACCGCUCUCCCCACACCCCACUUUUUUUUUUUUAACAAGUCCUCUCCCUCUAAAAGCCAGCAGGUUGAAGCUUUACGCAUCCAGAGGCAGAAAACUAAAGAUGGAACAGAAAAUGUAUCCAGGGUUUUCCAGAUGUGGGGAGAGGGGUUAAGGGAGCCCUGAGGAGAGGAGAGGGUAAGGGUCUUGGCAGAAUUGUGCCAAGGGCACACCAAGGCUUUGGCCAACCGGUCGCCCCUGCUAAGUAACAGUAAUCCAUGUAUACAGGCGAAAGUCUCUAAGAGGACAGAAGAGUAAAAAGGAAGAGUAGAGUUAAGAUGAUGAUCCCAGUUCUCCGUCUUGUACCCCAGGGAAGACCUGUGUAUCCUUCCAGGUUUCUUUAGGCACAUUUACAAGUACAUACACUUGGACAUAUAACCUUUUUUUCCUACAGCAUCAUGAUCAUAUUAGCCACACUUUCAGAGUAUAUACUUAAAAGGUCUUGCUAUAGUGGCACAGAUAUCUUUCAUUCUUUUUAGAUGACUUUUUUUUUUUUUAAGCACAGUCUCUCCACUACCUCUCUUUCCCUAACUCCCUAAUCUUUAACACAUUGGAGAGAAUUUAAGCCAGGGACAAGCACUCACACAAGUGACAUCCCUACCCUGACAGGCCUGCUUGGGUGGCAGGUCUACUCGUCAGUCCCAGGCUGGGCAUUUCCUGACAGAGGUCCAGGUCCGGCAGACAGCAAGGCACAGGAAGUGUCCUGCUGUGCUCACUGACUGCGUGGGCUGGCGGGGGUGGGGGGCUGCAAAUAUCCAUGUCGGACCUGAGCAGUCUCAGGCUUGCCAGCUCCAGGCAGGGAGGCUGAGAACUGGCUUUCAGCCUGGGGAGGAGUUUGGAGGAUUCGGGAGGGAGAGGUUUGUGGGGUUGGUGGUGGCGAGAGAAGAGGACAGGAGGAAGGAGAGUGUGAAGGGAGGCAAGGGGCUGUGGGCAGAGGGGAAAGGAAGGUGGCCUCGGGUGAGGGGAUACUCAGAGACUACUCAGCUGCCUGGGCCAGGCCCCUCUGCAGAUAAGUGUGGCUGGGGUGGUGGUAUGCAGGGCUGUGUGGGGCUCCCAGCUGACUGGCUGCGUCUGUAGCAGCCCCACUAUUCCUGCCCUGGGCCUCAAACCAGGAGCGUCCCAGGCCUUAGGUCAGCUAACCAAGGCCCGACAUUGCUGGCAGGGGUCUGCAGGGGUUUCUGUGGAUACUUUGACAUUUUUCACAAUAAACAUCCUCUGUUUUGA